GCGAGGUUUCAAGAUGGCGGUAGCUGAGGGGUUGACCGAGAGACCCAGUUGAAGGCCUUUACGAAGUGAAAGAGGCCGGGAGUCGCCCCCUACCCGCUUCUCGUAGUCCUGGGAGCACAGCAGAAGUGUUUUUCUUUUUUUAAUGAACAAGUAAACCAUACAAAUUGUCAACAUGGGACGGAGAUCUACAUCAUCCACCAAGAGUGGAAAAUUUAUGAACCCCACAGACCAAGCCCGAAAGGAAGCCCGGAAGAGAGAAUUAAAGAAGAACAAAAAACAGCGCAUGAUGGUUCGAGCUGCAGUUUUAAAGAUGAAGGAUCCAAAACAGAUAAUCCGAGACAUGGAGAAAUUGGAUGAAAUGGAGUUUAACCCAGUGCAACAGCCACAAUUAAAUGAGAAAGUACUGAAAGACAAGCGUAAAAAGCUGCGUGAAACCUUUGAACGUAUUCUACGACUCUAUGAAAAAGAGAAUCCAGAUAUUUACAAAGAAUUGAGAAAGCUAGAAGUAGAAUAUGAACAGAAGAGGGCUCAACUUAGCCAAUAUUUUGAUGCUGUCAAGAAUGCUCAGCAUGUGGAAGUGGAGAGUAUUCCUUUGCCAGAUAUGCCACAUGCUCCUUCCAACAUUUUGAUCCAGGACAUUCCACUUCCUGGUGCCCAGCCACCCUCUAUCCUAAAGAAAACCUCAGCCUAUGGACCUCCAACUCGGGCAGUUUCUAUCCUUCCUCUUCUUGGACAUGGUGUUCCACGUUUGCCCCCUGGCAGAAAACCUCCUGGCCCUCCCCCUGGUCCACCUCCUCCUCAAGUCGUGCAGAUGUAUGGCCGUAAAGUGGGUUUUGCCCUAGAUCUUCCCCCUCGUAGGCGAGAUGAAGACAUGUUAUAUAGUCCUGAACUUGCCCAGCGAGGUCAUGAUGAUGAUGUUUCUAGCACCAGUGAAGAUGAUGGCUAUCCUGAGGACAUGGAUCAAGAUAAGCAUGAUGACAGUACUGAUGACAGUGACACCGACAAAUCAGAUGGAGAAAGUGACGGGGAUGAAUUUGUGCACCGUGAUAAUGGUGAGAGAGACAACAAUGAAGAAAAGAAGUCAGGUCUGAGUGUACGGUUUGCAGAUAUGCCUGGAAAAUCAAGGAAGAAAAAGAAGAACAUGAAGGAACUGACUCCUCUUCAAGCCAUGAUGCUUCGUAUGGCAGGUCAAGAAAUCCCUGAGGAGGGACGGGAAGUAGAGGAAUUUUCAGAGGACGAUGAUGAAGAUGAUUCUGAUGACUCUGAAGCAGAAAAGCAAUCACAAAAGCAGCAUAAAGAGGAAUCCCAUUCUGAUGGCACAUCCACUGCUUCUUCACAGCAGCAGGCUCCGCCGCAGUCUGUUCCUCCUUCUCAGAUACAAGCACCUCCCAUGCCAGGACCACCACCUCUUGGACCACCACCUGCUCCACCAUUACGGCCUCCUGGGCCACCUACAGGCCUUCCUCCUGGUCCACCUCCAGGAGCUCCUCCAUUCCUGAGACCACCUGGAAUGCCAGGACUCCGAGGGCCCUUACCCCGACUUUUACCUCCAGGACCACCACCAGGCCGACCCCCUGGCCCUCCCCCAGGUCCACCUCCAGGUCUGCCUCCUGGUCCCCCUCCUCGUGGACCCCCACCAAGGCUACCUCCCCCUGCACCUCCAGGUAUUCCUCCACCUCGUCCUGGCAUGAUGCGCCCACCUUUGGUGCCUCCCCUUGGACCUGCCCCCCCUGGGCUGUUCCCACCAGCUCCCUUGCCAAACCCUGGGGUUUUAAGUGCCCCACCCAACUUGAUUCAGCGACCCAAGGCGGAUGAUACAAGUGCAGCCACCAUUGAGAAGAAAGCCACAGCAACCAUCAGUGCCAAGCCACAGAUCACUAAUCCCAAGGCAGAGAUUACUCGAUUUGUGCCCACUGCACUGAGAGUACGUCGGGAGAAUAAAGGGGCUACUGCUGCUCCCCAAAGAAAGUCAGAGGAUGAUUCUGCUGUGCCUCUUGCCAAAGCAGCACCCAAAUCUGGUCCUUCUGUUCCUGUCUCAGUACAAACUAAGGAUGAUGUCUAUGAGGCUUUCAUGAAAGAGAUGGAAGGGCUACUGUGACAGCUUUUGAUGCCAGAAAAGGCUUCUGUUCACAACAGUGGCCCAUGGAGAAAGAGGCUCUUAUUAAACUUAGAUGAAAGAGCUGCUUCCAUUGUCAGGGUAUUUUCUAAUUUCAGUUCAAGGAAUAUCCUAAAAUUUAGCCUUGUUCAGAAUUUACUGCACAUAAAAAAGGGUAUUUCAUCCAGAAUAGAUCAGUUAUUGAAGCAGUGCUGCUAACAUCCAUUCCCUUUCAUACCACCAUUUUCACCCUGUUUCUUCCCCUCCUCCAGUUCUUUGGAAAUUUGUGAUCGGGGGAUCUUAGUUGCUUAUUUGUUUUGACUCUUGUGUGCUGUGGGCACUGGAGUAGAGAUUUCUGGAGAAAAAAAAACAGUUUAUUUCAUCUUGCCUUUUGUGUUUGAGUUAUUUUUAAUAUUUUCCUGUAAAUAUUUUGUAAUAUUUUACUUGUAAUGAAAUGGAUCACAAUGUCAUUUCCUAAUACAAGGCAGGAUAUGUGGGAAGAAUAUGUACAAUUAUUUGAUUAAAAUUAUUUCCCACUGACCUAAACUUUCAGUGAUUUGUGGGAAAAAUAAAUAAAUGUUCUACACCAAGAUACUCUGUGUUACUGAUAAUAUGUAAACAUAAUACCUAUUUUAUGGACAGAAAAAGUUAAAUAUUUAAAACUUGGGUCUUUAAGGAACUGCCUUUCUGGUACAGAAUGAGAAUCUUACUGAAAACAUGGUAAAAACUACAUUUUAAAUUUUAAGGGAUAAAAAGGAGUAAUUAUUUCCCUUUUUUAAGAUUGUCAUACUGGCUUUAGAGAAACUGAGAGGUGUUAAGAAUAGUAUGGUUUGGCUUUUAUUAUUUAAAAGAUGUCUUACCUUCAGUGGUUACUUAUUCCAGAGCUUCUUGAACUGAUACGAGUUGAAUGGCAAAAGUCAUUUUAAACCAUUUUUAAGCUAUAAAAGAAUCAGAAGAGGUUAGCUUUUUUUCCUUUCUGAAUUGGUGGGUUUGGUGUGCUUUUAUAUUAAAAUAUGAAUGAAUAAGAGUGCUUAACAUUAAUUUGCAUUUAUACCAUUUUCUUUACAAAGUGCUUUAAUGUAAACUCAUCUACCAAUUUAGACUAACUCUUAGUAAGUUUAAUGUUAAUUUAAUGACUAACUCAUCUACCAAUUAACCCUAUAGAUAACUUUUCUGGGUAUUUUCCCCAUUUUACAUUAGAGAGUAUUGAAACUUAAAAAGGACUCGUGAUUUAUCCAGUGAUCCAAAGUGUGUAUUUCAUAAACACAUACACACAGUGCGUGCAUUGUUUAGGCAUACGUUACUUUCCACAGUAUCUCAAAUGCCUUUUACAUGAAUCCCAUACUAUCAAAAAUUGGUGAUAACCUAAAAUGUAGUGCAAUAAUACAAUAAGGCAUUUAUUUUCUUAGAGUUGAGUUGAUGGAUUUUUAGAUUUUUAUUCAAGAUCUUUUGUUUGUUUGGCUUUGCUUGGAAGAUACUGAUUUAUUCUUUCAUAUUAAAGCAAAUCCUGCCAAAGCACUAAAUAGACCGUUUUGGGUUGGUUUUUUAGUGUAAUAUUAAUACGGGUCCACAGGUGAAUUGAGUCUGUUCAGAUGUAAGGAUUGAACCUUAUGUUAUCAAUCCUUGACACCAUCCUUGAUAACUUACGGAUAUCAAGGAUCAAACCAUAUGGUAUCAAUAUUGUUAGUUAUUCAGCAUAAACAGAAUUAUUUCCCAAUACUUGAUCUGAAAUAUUUUUAAUGGUCUUACUUGAAACUUAUAUUCUUUCUGGGAGUGAUGUUUUUAUCAUUUUUCCAUGGAGACAGGUUCUAACUCUGUUGCCCAGGCUGCAGUGCAGUGAUGUGAUCAUAGCUCACUGCAGCCUGAAACUCCUGGGUUCAAGUGAUCUCUGGCCUCAGCCUCCCAAGUAGUUGGAACUUCAGAUACGUGCCACCACAACCAGCUAAUUUAUUUUUUAGAGAUGAGGUCUCGCUAUGUUGCCCAGUCUGGUCUCCUAGCCUCAAGUGAUCUUCCCAUCUCAGCCUUCAGUUGGAGAUUUCUGAUUUAUGUUAAUAUAAGAAAGCUGUUGAUAGUUUAUCAUAAAGGCAUUUCCUUAUAUUGCUAGUAUAAUUUUCUGAAAAUUAGUGGUGUGACAAUACAUCAGCUGCAUCCACAGGAAAGGGGAAUUAAUUAGCAGUUCUGAUUCUGGGUACACUUGUUAUGAUCAUAAUUUACAUAAUAUUUUCAUGAAAAUGGUCAGCUCACAGCUAUGAAAUGUAAAUGAUAGAAAUCUUUAAUCAUGUAUAUGGAUAGACUUGUUACUAUUUCCUUAUCAAAGUGUCACUUUAGGGACAGCAGUUGCCCCUUUAAAUUAAGGAUCACCACAAUAAUACUCUGCCAUGUCAUGGAAUCAGCAUGAAGCCCUGGAUGCUAUCCAAGAUUCUGUUUCAGUUCUCAUUUUGUAUAUUCUUGUUUGUGCUCUUGAUUAAAAUAUCUCCUUAUAUAUA